GCCGGCGUCCCCAACAUGGCGGCUCCCCAAGACGUCCACGUCCGGAUCUGUAACCAAGAGAUUGUCAAAUUUGACCUGGAGGUGAAGGCGCUUAUUCAGGAUAUCCGUGAUUGUUCAGGACCCUUAAGUGCUCUUACUGAACUGAAUACUAAAGUAAAAGAGAAAUUUCAACAGUUGCGUCACAGAAUACAGCCAGUUCUCUAUCAAAGGGCAUUUAUUUGGACUGCUUCCACAUUUUUUUUUAAGCUAACUUAUUCCCUGACAGACUUUUCUUCAACUCAGCAUGACUUCAACUCUCCAACUACACCUGUUACCUUCAGUGACCUGGAGCAGUUGGCUAAAGAGCAAGACAAAGAAUCAGAGAAACAACUUCUACUCCAGGAAGUGGAGAAUCACAAAAAGCAGAUGCUCAGCAAUCAGGCCUCAUGGAGGAAAGCUAAUCUCACCUGCAAAAUUGCAAUCGACAAUCUAGAGAAAGCAGAACUUCUUCAGGGAGGAGAUCUCUUAAGGCAAAGGAAAACCACCAAAGAGAGCCUGGCCCAGACAUCCAGUACCAUCACUGAGAGCCUCAUGGGGAUCAGCAGGAUGAUGGCCCAGCAGGUCCAGCAGAGCGAGGAGGCCAUGCAGUCUCUAGGUAACACAUACAGCAUAGAGAAGGAUAAGAAAACUCUAGCCCAGGACUGCCAUAGAAACGCAACAGCAGCCACUCACUUCUUCACGAACGAUCCUGGAUGCAAAUGAAGAAUUUAAGUCCAUGUCGGGCACCAUCCAGCUGGGCCGGAAGCUUAUCACAAAAUACAAUCGCCGGGAGCUGACGGACAAGCUUCUCAUCUUCCUUGCGCUAGCCCUGUUUCUUGCUACGGUCCUCUAUAUUGUGAAAAAGCGGCUCUUUCCAUUUUUGUGAGAUCCCAAAGGUGCCAGUUCUGGCCCUUUCAGCUCCUGUUUCAGGAUCUGUCCUGGUUCCUGAGCUCUAGGCUGCUAAGCUGAGCCACACACCCCUCCGUUUGCACCAGUUGCCUGCAGGUUGGAUGGAACACAGUGCCCCACUUUUCUGCAAGUAGCUGGCUUGUAAAGGGUGAACAGAGCCAUGGGAGGAAGGUCUGGCAUUGGGAUGCCGCCCUGGGGACAUACGAACCGCCUCCUUCCACCAUUGUGCACUAUGGGAGGCCGCUGCUGCGUGGAGCACUUAAAGUCCAGCCUCCAGGACCGGAUGCCCCUCCUGUCUCCCGCUCCCAUCGUGCCCUUAAAUGCCAGAUCUGGUGGAGGGAAGAGAGAAGAGGUAGGAAGAAAGGUGAUGAAAACUCCUGGUCAUUCCUUGAAUAAACUUGAUUUUAUUUAAUAGAAUAAAAUGUAUUUGAUUUUGUAAGAUA